ACCCGCGGCGGCCUCCUCGGUGCGCGACCCCCGGCUCAGAGGACUCUUUGCUGUCCCGCAAGAUGCGGAUGCUGCUGGCGCUCCUGGCCCUCUCCGCGGCGCGGCCAUCGGCCAGUGCAGAGUCACACUGGUGCUACGAGGUUCAAGCCGAGUCCUCCAACUACCCCUGCUUGGUGCCAGUCAAGUGGGGUGGAAACUGCCAGAAGGACCGCCAGUCCCCCAUCAACAUCGUCACCACCAAGGCAAAGGUGGACAAAAAACUGGGACGCUUCUUCUUCUCUGGCUACGAUAAGAAGCAAACGUGGACUGUCCAAAAUAACGGGCACUCAGUGAUGAUGUUGCUGGAGAACAAGGCCAGCAUUUCUGGAGGAGGACUGCCUGCCCCAUACCAGGCCAAACAGUUGCACCUGCACUGGUCCGACUUGCCAUAUAAGGGCUCGGAGCACAGCCUCGAUGGGGAGCACUUUGCCAUGGAGAUGCACAUAGUACAUGAGAAAGAGAAGGGGACAUCGAGGAAUGUGAAAGAGGCCCAGGACCCUGAAGACGAAAUUGCGGUGCUGGCCUUUCUGGUGGAGAUCGGGAGAAUGAACUGGCCACCACCACUGGCUCCCUGCAGACUUUCUCAAGACCCUUCCCUCCCUUUCCAGGCUGGAACCCAGGUGAACGAGGGCUUCCAGCCACUGGUGGAGGCACUGUCUAAUAUCCCCAAACCUGAGAUGAGCACUACGAUGGCAGAGAGCAGCCUGUUGGACCUGCUCCCCAAGGAGGAGAAACUGAGGCACUACUUCCGCUACCUGGGCUCACUCACCACACCGACCUGCGAUGAGAAGGUCGUCUGGACUGUGUUCCGGGAGCCCAUUCAGCUUCACAGAGAACAGAUCCUGGCAUUCUCUCAGAAGCUGUACUACGACAAGGAACAGACAGUGAGCAUGAAGGACAAUGUCAGGCCCCUGCAGCAGCUGGGGCAGCGCACGGUGAUAAAGUCCGGGGCCCCGGGUCGGCCGCUGCCCUGGGCCCUGCCUGCCCUGCUGGGCCCCAUGCUGGCCUGCCUGCUGGCCGGCUUCCUGCGAUGAUGGCUCACUUCUGCACGCAGCCUCUCUGUUGCCUCAGCUCUCCAAGUUCCAGGCUUCCGGUCCUUAGCCUUCCCAGCUGCUAAGGUCCCUGGGCCAUCAGAAGCGAAUAGAACAAACCUAAGACAUCACUCUCCAUCAAGAGGCCUGCAUGACUCUUUAUUUACAUCAUCUUCCAGGAAGAGGAGGAGGAGCUGCUUUGGGGACACCCACUUCCUCUCCUUACGUAACAACACACUGCAUUUGCACAAGUGUCCUUGGUUGUAAAGGGUUCCACACUCACUUUCUUAUUCAGGGCUUAUUACAAGCCUCUCAGGUAGCUAUGGUCAUGGUACCCUGAUCCCUUGUCAAAGAUGAGCCCACUGAGGCUCAGGGUGACUACCGUUGUGCCAGGAGUUGCUAAGUGGUGGAUCACAGACUCCAGUUCAGGGGGAGGUAGGGUGGUAAAGAAGCAGCUGGAUGAACCUGGGUUUGAAUCCUGCUCAGAAAUGUUCCAUCUGUGUGACACCACAGGCAAGUGACUUAACCUGAUUGAGCCUCAGCUUCCUGAUCUAGAAAAAAGGGUGAUCAUGCAUCCCUCAUAGAGCUGUGGUGAGCAUUUACGAAUCACGAGUGAAACAUGCAUAGCAUGGGGUUUGGCAGAUAGAAGUCCAGUAAAUGUCUAAGCCCAUCUCCAGCGUUUCUUCUGGUUCCAAGCUCAGGACUAUCCUUUAAGCUAAGUGGUAGAUACUCAAUGAACGUGUUUUGGAUGAUUUAGCCCUCUCCUUUCCCCCAUCCCUCCCCAAGUGAGAGGAUGUUUAUUUGCAGCUCUGUGCUGCAGAGAGCUCUGCAAACAAGGAUUGGCAGCAGUAACUUUCUCCAGCUGGCACAACAAUGAAAGGCCACAGGCCCUGGGGCUGCUCCCUAUGGAUGUCCAGGGAACAGAGGCCAGGCAGCAGGCUGACUGCUCCGGGCACUCCCUGUGGCUUCUUCACUCUAGCUGGCUACCCAGUAUACUGAGUAGCAAAAUGGCCUUUGAAAAGGCCCACCCUGUGGCCAUGAUUUCUAGCAGACCAAAUGAGAGUGUUCUCCUGGGAGCACUGUCAACUCCUCUUGCUGGAGACAAUUCUCUGGGAGCUCCUCAGACCCUACUGGAGCACUGUGUGCUUGGCUUUCUGAAUGCUUAGAGGUGACAGGUGCUUUAGCAGACAUCCAAUCCACAGCGGUUGCCCAGGCAGCACUACACCCCCCACUGUCACUUCAACCGGAGUAACUCCAACCUCAUCUGCUUUAGCUAUGGGUCCUUCAGGUAAAUGUGGCUGGAAUGGCUGGAAGAAAGGGUCGGGUCUCAAUGUUGUUUCAAAAUAAAAGCUGAAGACAACUGACCUAAUGCAACUCGCUCAAUAUUCACAGGGGGAACCGAGGCGCGGACAAGGCAAGUGACCCCCAAGGUCAUACAAUUCUGCCAAGUGCUGAGCAAACACUGCGGACUGGACUUCUGGUCUACUGCUUUCCAUGGCAUCAGCUAAGAUGACUGCUCUGAACCUGGGGCUGCGGCAGCCUCUGAUGAUGGCCGUGAACAAAUAGAAGCUGAGGGUGAAGGACCUACAGCUGUCACCUUCAUCUCUUCUCAACACUGCCAACUGUCUCCUUGGAUCUCCCAGACAGACGACUAGGGACAUCUCUGGUUUCUCGGUGCUCCCUAGAAACCUAGGGUCAUUUCAAGGCAUUAUGCAAAUGAGCUUUCCUUCUCUUCACCUCAUCUCCUGAUCUGCACAAAAAUGACCGUAGGACCCACUGUAGGUACCAAUGUAGGCACCAAUCCUCAGUUUACCACCUGCUCUCUACUUGCUUCCCUGCCAUAACUUUCUAAAAGGGAUGUGAGCCAUGUUUAAAGUCACCUGGUCACUGGAGGGAUCUUGUUCUACACUCUACAUCAGUGGUUGCCAACCUUUUUGGCACCAGGGACUGGUGUUGUGGAAGACAAUUUUUCCACGGACUGGGGGAUGGGGGGAGUGGUUUCAGGAUAAAACUGCUCCACCUCAAAUCAUCAGGCAUUAGAUUCUCAUAAGGAGCACACAACCUAGAUUGCUAGCAGGCACAGUUCACAAUAGGGUUCGUUCUCCUGUGAGAAUGGCAUGCCGCUGCUGAUCUAACAGAGGCAGAGCUCAGGUGGUAAUGGGAGCAAGGGGGAGCGGCUCUAAAUACAGCUUGCCGCUCACCUCCUGCUGUGCAGCCCAGUUCCUAACAGGCCACAGAUGGUACUGGUCUGUAGCCCAGGAGUUUGGGAAUCCUGCUCUACAGAGUUUCCAACCUCAGAGAUGAAGCAUCCCCUCUGUAAGUCAGAAAGAAAUUAUUCAAGUAGGAGAAUUAAAACAGGAUCACAGAGAGGGAGGCUGAAGAAUUUGUCUUUCUGUGUUUACUUGUAUGAGGAAAAACGGCACAUGGAGGCAUCCACAGUAUUUAAUUUGUUUGUAUACUAGUUACAGAUAAACAGGUACACCCCAUAUACAAUUACCAAUACUUUUUAUACAGUUCAUAUUUCGGUACAUCAACACUAUUUUAUUUACACUCUAUUUAUGUACAUUAACAUCUUUCUAAAGUCAGUGCAUUGUCAACAAGUUUUAUACAGUAAUUUACAAGGUGAAUGUAGUUAAUAGUUAAUUUAAUAAAUUUUCUGCUAGUUCAUGAAUUAAAAAAAUUAAUUACAACCAGUAUAACAAACACAGAUCAAACAACAUUAGUAGAUUGAGCUACCUGCUUAAAUAAAACAUCUGUAAAGAAAUUAUUUAAAAUCUUCCACUUUUUAAUGGGAAUGGACAGAUUUUAUAUACUGAAAAUCUUGAAACUAUAAAGUAUGCAUUUUGUCUGACUUUAUUACAUUAGACAAUUUAGGCCAGUCCUACCUACUUGCAAUUAUAUUUUUUCUGAAAAGGAUUUCAAUUUAGGUAGCCAUUUAAGAUAACCUUUCCAAAUGCUCUGAGAACUAGAUAUUAAUAGUUACUGGCCUCAGAUAUCAGAACACAAAUACUUAGUUACAUUGGUAAUUACUAUCUAUGAGGAAGAAAGGGUAGUGGAAUCUGACAAUUAAUGAGAAUCAACUUGCAGGGUCUAAAUGAAUAAACAAAGACCAAAAAUAAGGUGAAACAUUUCCUUCAAGUAUAUAUUAAAAAACUACACGAAAAAAAUGCUACCUGAAAUAAAUAAUAUUUAUACUUUUGUUCCAGUCUUGAUUAGAGAAAAAAAUGAAGUAAGCAAAGAAACAUAACUUUCGAUGACUACUGUAAAAUUUAAAAAAAAGACAAAUAUCAAAAUAAAAAAAUUAGUGGACAUGCAAACAAAGCAAAACUAAAGUUGACUUCCUAAAACCACCAAUUUCAUUAAAUACACUUAUGAACUCCUAA